ACUUGCUAACCACAAAACCCGCCAGGCCGGUGCGGGAGCUGCGGAGCAUCCGCUGCGGUCCUCGCCGAGACCCCCGCGCGGAUUCGCCGGUCCUUCCCGCGGGCGCGACAGAGCUGUCCUCGCACCUGGAUGGCAGCAGGGGCGCCGGGGUCCUCUCGACGCCAGAGAGAAAUCUCAUCAUCUGUGCAGCCUUCUUAAAGCAAACUAAGACCAGAGGGAGGAUUAUCCUUGACCUUUGAAGACCAAAACUAAACUGAAAUUUAAAAUGUUCUUCGGGGGAGAAGGGAGCUUGACUUACACUUUGGUAAUAAUUUGCUUCCUGACACUAAGGCUGUCUGCUAGUCAGAAUUGCCUCAAAAAGAGUCUAGAAGAUGUUGUCAUUGACAUCCAGUCAUCUCUUUCUAAGGGAAUCAGAGGCAAUGAGCCCGUAUAUACUUCAACUCAAGAAGACUGCAUUAAUUCUUGCUGUUCAACAAAAAACAUAUCAGGGGACAAAGCAUGUAACUUGAUGAUCUUCGACACUCGAAAAACAGCUAGACAACCCAACUGCUACCUAUUUUUCUGUCCCAACGAGGAAGCCUGUCCAUUGAAACCAGCAAAAGGACUUAUGAGUUACAGGAUAAUUACAGAUUUUCCAUCUUUGACCAGAAAUUUGCCAAGCCAAGAGUUACCCCAGGAAGAUUCUCUCUUACAUGGCCAAUUUUCACAAGCAGUCACUCCCCUAGCCCAUCAUCACACAGAUUAUUCAAAGCCCACCGAUAUCUCAUGGAGAGACACACUUUCUCAGAAGUUUGGAUCCUCAGAUCACUUGGAGAAACUAUUUAAGAUGGAUGAAGCAAGUGCCCAGCUCCUUGCUUAUAAGGAAAAAGGCCAUUCUCAGAGUUCACAAUUUUCCUCUGAUCAAGAAAUAGCUCAUCUGCUGCCUGAAAAUGUGAGUGCGCUCCCAGCUACGGUGGCAGUUGCUUCUCCACAUACCACCUCGGCUACUCCAAAGCCCGCCACCCUUCUACCCACCAAUGCUUCAGUGACACCUUCUGGGACUUCCCAGCCACAGCUGGCCACCACAGCUCCACCUGUAACCACUGUCACUUCUCAGCCUCCCACGACCCUCAUUUCUACAGUUUUUACACGGGCUGCGGCUACACUCCAAGCAAUGGCUACAACAGCAGUUCUGACUACCACCUUUCAGGCACCUACGGACUCGAAAGGCAGCUUAGAAACCAUACCGUUUACAGAAAUCUCCAACCUAACUUUGAACACAGGGAAUGUGUAUAACCCUACUGCACUUUCUAUGUCAAAUGUGGAGUCUUCCACUAUGAAUAAAACUGCUUCCUGGGAAGGUAGGGAGGCCAGUCCAGGCAGUUCCUCCCAGGGCAGUGUUCCAGAAAAUCAGUACGGCCUUCCAUUUGAAAAAUGGCUUCUUAUCGGGUCCCUGCUCUUUGGUGUCCUGUUCCUGGUGAUAGGCCUCGUCCUCCUGGGUAGAAUCCUCUCGGAAUCACUCCGCAGGAAACGUUACUCAAGACUGGAUUAUUUGAUCAAUGGGAUCUAUGUGGACAUCUAAGGAUGGAACUCGGUGUCUCUUAAUUCAUUUAGUAACCAGAAGCCCAAAUGCAAUGAGUUUCUGCUGACUUGCUAGUCUUAGCAGGAGGUUGUAUUUUGAAGACAGGAAAAUGCCCCCUUCUGCUUUCCUUUUUUUUUUUUGGAGACAGAGUCUUGCUUUGUUGCCCAGGCUGGAGUGCAGUAGCACGAUCUCGGCUCUCACCGCAACCUCCGUCUCCUGGGUUCAAGCGAUUCUCCUGCCUCAGCCUCCUAAGUAUCUGGGAUUACAGGCAUGUGCCACCACACCUGGGUGAUUUUUGUAUUUUUAGUAGAGACGGGGUUUCACCAUGUUGGUCAGGCUGGUCUCAAACUCCUGACCUAGUGAUCCACCCUCCUCGGCCUCCCAAAGUGCUGGGAUUACAGGCAUGAGCCACCACAGCUGGCCCCCUUCUGUUUUAUGUUUGGUUUUUGAGAAGGAAUGAAGUGGGAACCAAAUUAGGUAAUUUUGGGUAAUCUGUCUCUAAAAUAUUAGCUAAAAACAAAGCUCUAUGUAAAGUAAUAAAGUAUAAUUGCCAUAUAAAUUUCAAAAUUCAACUGGCUUUUAUGCAAAGAAACAGGUUAGGACAUCUAGGUUCCAAUUCAUUCACAUUCUUGGUUCCAGAUAAAAUCAACUGUUUAUAUCAAUUUCUAAUGGAUUUGCUUUUCUUUUUAUAUGGAUUCCUUUAAAACUUAUUCCAGAUGUAGUUCCUUCCAAUUAAAUAUUUGAAUAAAUCUUUUGUUACUCAGUAGUGUUCUCAUAAGUAGCAUGUCCAGCUGGAUAACUUUCCAUUUAUUUCCACUAGCAAAAUGAUUAUGUGGUGAAAAUAUGCGUUCCACGUUAAAAUGACAACCCCCCCUUUUUCCCAUCAGUGAGCAAAGAGCUUCACUUGGGAGAAUCUAGCGGAAUGUUAGCCCACAUGGAGACAAUGAUAAGUCAGUUCUGAUAAAUGGCCAUAUCCACUUGGGAUCUGUUCUAGUUAACUUGUGUGUGUGUGUGUGUGUGUGUGUGUGUGUGUGUGUGUGUGACAGAGUCUUGCUCUGUCACCCAGGCUAGAGUGCAGUGGCGCGAUCUCGGCUCACUGCCAGCUCCGCCUCCUGGGUUCCCGCCAUUCUCCUGCCUCAGCCUCCCAAGUAGCUGGGACUACAGGCGCCCGCCAACACGCCCAGCUAAUUUUUUAUAUUUUUAGUAAAGACGGGGUUUCACUGUGUUAGUCAGGAUGGUCUCGAUCUCCUGACCUUGUGAUCCGCCCGCCUCGGCCUCCCAAAGUGCUGGGAUUACAGGCGUGAGCCACCGUGCCCGGCCUCUAGUUAACUUUUUAAAGAAGUAUUAUAGACAUUUUCUAAACUUGUACUAAGUUAAAAAUGUACCACUAUUAUUUUAUAUCCUUACUUAAAUUGACCAGCAAUCAGUCUAAGCUUAAUUUAGAACAACAUUGGAAAUAAUAACUAGCACAGGCCAGGCGCGGUGGCUCACGCCUGUAAUCCCAGCACUUUGGGAGGCCGAGAUGGGCAAAUCACGAGGUCAGGAGAUCGAGACCAUCCUGGCUAACACGGUGAAACCCCGCCUCUACUAAAAAUACAAAAAAUUAGCCGGGCGUGGUGGCGGGCGCCUGUAGUUCCAGCUACUUGGGAGGCUGAGGCAGGAGAGUAGUUUGAAUCCAGGAGGCGGAGGUUGCGGUGAGCCAGAUUGCACCAUUGCGCUCCAGCCUGGGCAACAGAGCCAGACUCCGUCUCAAAAAUAAUAAUAAUAAUAACUAGCACUAACAUGAUGCUACAAUUUUUACUGGUUACCAAUUAAAAUUUCUGAGAAAGGCUUUUAAUAAAGUUUUCCAGACAAGUUAUAGGUGAGGUAACAAAGAGUCCAGAAGUCCCCUGGGUCAGUUUGAUACCUCUUUCCUCUGGACUUCAAUUUGCUUAUCUGCAAAACAGGAAAUUUGAUCCCUUCCAAGUGUCACCAGAGUUUUUAAAGAUAAAAAUGGAAUUCAGAUGCGAACUUAAUACAGUGAGCACUAGAGGGCAGUAGCUGGUUAAUAAGUACAGCAAUUAAGACAAAUGCAGGAAAUGACAGAAAAGGCUUUUCUUCUCCUUCCUCCUCACCUCUUCCUUCCUCCUCACCUCCUUCCCCUCUGCUCUUCUGGUACCCCUCCCCCAUUUCCCUGGUUUACACUAAGUUCAUAAAGUACAUUAAGAGGAAAGCUGGUCUAUUGAAAAUACUACUUUUCUUAUAUUUUCCAACUUAACAGCUUGACACAAAUCUCCAAGGGGUUUACAUAAGCUUUAAGUAGGCUGAAUAAAUAAAACCUUGAGUCAAUUUAACUUAACAAGUAUUUAUUGAAUAUCCACAUGUAGGCCAGAAUCAGAUUAGUAACCAGGUGCCUUGGAAUUUUAAAAUUUCUCCUCUCUUUAUUAAUGGAUUUAGCGAGUGGAAAUCAGGCUUUCUGUGAUGGUUUAUAAAGGUAUUUUCCUGGCUCUCUUGGAGUUCUCUGUCCACCUUGCUGCAGUCUUUGUUGUGAUGGGGAGACCACAUGGGAGCGGUCCAGAUGAGUGAUGCUACGGGCCCAAACUGUUAGUGGCCGUGAGGAUAUAGGUUGUAGGGGACAUCUGGAGUGGAAAGAGUGCUCUUCUCACACAGCUCUCUCUACUUACUGCCCCUAGGAUGGUGGGUGCAACUGUGGCAAGGGCAGUCAGGGUAGGGGAAUCCCUUAGAGGAAUUCAGCAGUGACUAGUCUGGUUAGCCUUUCCCACAAGGCCCAUUGAGUUAUGAGCCCCCUCCUUUGGUUUGUAGAAAGAGAAGGUAGCAGCCUAGAACAGGUGAGAAGAUGAGGUAGGUCCUUCUGCUCAAACAUCCUCUCUCCGUAUUUUACCAACACGAUACUGACCUAGGUUAAAAAGCUACUCUUGGCCAGGCGUGGUGGCUCACGCCUGUAAUCCCAGCACUUUGGGAGUCCAAGGUGGGUGGAUCACCUGAGGUCAGGAGUUCUAGACCAGCCUGGCCAACAUGGUGAAACCCCAUCUCUACAGAAAUACAAAAAUUAGCCAGGCAUGGUGGCAGACACCUGUAAUCCCAGCUACUUGGGAGGCUGAGGUAGGAUAAUUGCUUGAGGCCGGGAGGGGGCGGUUGCAGUGAGCCAAGAUCGCUCCAUUGCACUCCAGCCUAGGCGACAGAGCAAGACUCUAUCUCAAAAAAAUAAAAUAAAAUAAAAUAAAAAUAAGCUACUCUUAGCCAGGCACAUAGUGGCUCACAUCUGUAAUCUCAGCCCUUUGGGAGACUGAGGUGGGAGGAUCACUUGAGCCCAGGAGGUCGAGGCUGCAGUGAGCCAUGAUCACGCCACUGCACUCCAGCCUGGGCGACAGAACGAGAGCCCAUCUCAAAAAAAAAAACAAAACAACAACAACAAAAAAAAAACUAAAAAACUCUUAAAAAACCUGAGGACUCCUGGAUGAAUACUGUUAUGUGCCUGUUUCUCAAUUACCCCUGGCCUGAGUGAGGAACUUUUGGAACUCUUUGGCUCCCAGACUGUGGUGGGCACUACCGGUCAGCUGCCCAGCAGCCAGCCCUAGUCCCACUUCUGCCUCAUUUGUUACAGGUUGGAAGUGCCAGGUUCAGGGAUGGGCCUGUGACCCAAGUUUUAGCUGAAAGGAAACCUACUAGGGACUUCUAGGAGAGAUUUUCUUGCUUGUAAAGGGAAGGCUGCACAAGGAGAAAAGCCCUUUCUAACCACAUCCCCUUAUUUCAUGCUUGGGAUGCUGACCAUGUGAAGACUUGGUUGUUGGAGCUGUGGUGGCCUCCCUGCCAUGAUGAGGGGAGAAGGCACUGCCACACUGAGCGUGGCAGUGGGUACAGGAAGAGUCCAGUCUCCGGGAUGCCUUGGUUAAUUGACAGGACAAACCCUGGAACUGCCAACUUCCAUCUUGUUCUGUAAUAAUAAAUCUCUAAUAUUUGUACCACUUUCA